CUCCGCCACCAUCUUGCUUUCCUUUAAUCCGGCAGUGACCGUGUGUCAGAACAAUCUUGAAUCAUGAAGCUACUAACCAGAGCCGGCUCUUUCUCGAGAUUUUAUUCCCUCAAAGUUGCCCCCAAAGUUAAAGCCACAGCUGCGCCUGCAGGAGCACCGCCACAACCUCAGGACCUUGAGUUUACCAAGUUACCAAAUGGCUUGGUGAUUGCUUCUUUGGAAAACUAUUCUCCUGUAUCAAGAAUUGGUUUGUUCAUUAAAGCAGGCAGUAGAUAUGAGGACUUCAGCAAUUUAGGAACCACCCAUUUGCUGCGUCUUACAUCCAGUCUGACGACAAAAGGAGCUUCAUCUUUCAAGAUAACCCGUGGAAUUGAAGCAGUUGGUGGCAAAUUAAGUGUGACCGCAACAAGGGAAAACAUGGCUUAUACUGUGGAAUGCCUGCGGGGUGAUGUUGAUAUUCUAAUGGAGUUCCUGCUCAAUGUCACCACAGCACCAGAAUUUCGUCGUUGGGAAGUAGCUGACCUUCAGCCUCAGCUAAAGAUUGACAAAGCUGUGGCCUUUCAGAAUCCGCAGACUCAUGUCAUUGAAAAUUUGCAUGCAGCAGCUUACCGGAAUGCCUUGGCUAAUCCCUUGUAUUGUCCUGACUAUAGGAUUGGAAAAGUGACAUCAGAGGAGUUACAUUACUUCGUUCAGAACCAUUUCACAAGUGCAAGAAUGGCUUUGAUUGGACUUGGUGUGAGUCAUCCUGUUCUAAAGCAAGUUGCUGAACAGUUUCUCAACAUGAGGGGUGGGCUUGGUUUAUCUGGUGCAAAGGCCAACUACCGUGGAGGUGAAAUCCGAGAACAGAAUGGAGACAGUCUUGUCCAUGCUGCUUUUGUAGCAGAAAGUGCUGUCGCGGGAAGUGCAGAGGCAAAUGCAUUUAGUGUUCUUCAGCAUGUCCUCGGUGCUGGGCCACAUGUCAAGAGGGGCAGCAACACCACCAGCCAUCUGCACCAGGCUGUUGCCAAGGCAACUCAGCAGCCAUUUGAUGUUUCUGCAUUUAAUGCCAGUUACUCAGAUUCUGGACUCUUUGGGAUUUAUACUAUCUCCCAGGCCACAGCUGCUGGAGAUGUUAUCAAGGCUGCCUAUAAUCAAGUAAAAACAAUAGCUCAAGGAAACCUUUCCAACACAGAUGUCCAAGCUGCCAAGAACAAGCUGAAAGCUGGAUACCUAAUGUCAGUGGAGUCUUCUGAGUGUUUCCUGGAAGAAGUCGGGUCCCAGGCUCUAGUUGCUGGUUCUUACAUGCCACCAUCCACAGUCCUUCAGCAGAUUGAUUCAGUGGCUAAUGCUGAUAUCAUAAAUGCGGCAAAGAAGUUUGUUUCUGGCCAGAAGUCAAUGGCAGCAAGUGGAAAUUUGGGACAUACACCUUUUGUUGAUGAGUUGUAAUACUGAUGCACACAUUACAGGAGAGAGCUGAACGUUCUCUCAGCCCAGAGCAGCAAACACAUGAAAGUCAGAAGUCUCUAAUAUAUCAUUUGUCUUUUUUCCAGUGAGGUAAAAUAAGGCAUAAAUGCAGGUAAUUAUUCCCAGCUGACCUAAAGUCAAUAAAACAUUCUGUUUAAGUGUUUUUCUUACGUUUUUCUCAAUGAGUUAAUCAACAAGUAUUUAUUAUGUGCUGAUAUCUUUGUUUUAGAUGCUUUAAAGGAGACAGGAAUAUAAUUAUUGAGUAUAGAAGCAUCAGAAACUAUUAAAAUUAAGGCUAAGUGGCUAUCGGGGUAAAUAGUGCCAGAUUACUAUUGGUGGCGUUUAAGAUGAAAGCAAGUUCAAAAUUUGUCAUUUUGGGUGUCAACAGCUAAAUGGUCUGGUUUUUACCCCUGUUUUGCCUUUUUUGCAAUAAAAUUAUUUCCAAAAAACAUACAUUUCCUAUCAAUCAUA